GCCGCCCCCGUUUCUUCUCCUUACAUCGCGCCUCGCCUCGCUCCUCGUCCUAAUGUCUGCACACCCCUCUGGUGUCUGUCGACCCUCCCAAUCGCUUCUCCCGCAUUCAUCUCUCGCCUGAUCCCGGUUCUGUCCGCCCAUGCUCAUUUCUCUCCCCCAGCCGUGCCCGGGCGCGUUUCCAUUACUCUCCCAUCGUCGCCCACCGCGCGUGGGGCGGCCAACUUGGGCCCACGCAGCUCAGCUCCCUCCGCCCUUCCUGCCUCCUGGCGCCUGUUGCUCCCCACACUCUGCCGCCCCCCGCCCGCCCUCCCCAGCCUCUCUGCCCACCCAUCUCUACGUUUCUCACCCUCUGACCGUUUCUCUCCCGCCCAGCGCUCCAACCUCUGCUCUCGUUCUCCCCGCAGCCUGGCGGCCCAGUGCGACCCCCUGCAAGCCCCAUGCCGGCCCUCCUGCUCCUCGUACUCCUGGCCUCUAGCGCCGGCCAGGCCAGGGCGCGCCCGUCCAACGCCACGAGCGCCGAGCCCGCGGGCCCGCUGCCCGCCCUGCUGGCGCACCUGCGGCGCCUGACCGGGGCGCUGACGGGCGGCGGGGGCGCGGCGAGCCCAGGCGCCAACGGCACCAGGACCGGCCCCGCGGGCGGGGCGGGCGCGGCGGCCCGGGCGCCCCCUCCCGCCGAGCUCUGCCACGGCUACUACGAUGUCAUGGGCCAGUACGACGCCACCUUCAACUGCAGCACCGGCUCCUACCGCUUCUGCUGUGGCACCUGCCACUACCGCUUCUGCUGUGAGCACCGUCACAUGCGCCUGGCGCAGGCCUCCUGCUCCAACUACGACACGCCGCGCUGGGCCACCACGCCGCCGCCGCUAGCUGGGGGCGCCGGGGGCGCUGGGGGUGCGGGCGGGGGGCCAGGGCCCGGCCAGGCCGGGUGGUUGGAAGGGGGCCGGACUGGGGGUGCCGGGGGCCGCGGGGGCGAGGGCCCCGGGGGCAGCACAGCCUACGUCGUGUGCGGGGUCAUCAGCUUCGCCCUGGCCGUGGGCGUCGGCGCCAAAGUGGCCUUCAGCAAGGCGUCCCGUGCGCCCCGGGCGCACCGGGAUAUCAACGUGCCCAGAGCUCUGGUGGACAUUCUGAGACAUCAGGCGGGGCCUGGGACCCGCCCGGACCGGGCCCGAAGCAGCUCCCUGACCCCGGGGAUCGGCGGUCCCGACAGCAUGCCCCCCAGGACGCCCAAGAACCUCUACAACACCGUGAAGACCCCCAACCUCGACUGGCGAGCCUUGCCGCCGCCCAGCCCCUCCUUGCACUACUCCACGCUGUCCUGCUCUCGGUCCUUCCACAACCUCUCGCAUCUGCCCCCGUCCUACGAGGCUGCCGUGAAAUCCGAGCUGAACCGCUACUCUUCCCUCAAGAGGCUGGCCGAGAAGGAUCUGGACGAGGCCUACCUGAAGCGCCGGCCCCUGGAAUUGCCCCGCGGCACGCUGCCCCUGCACGCGCUGCGGCGGCCGGGCACGGGGGGCGGCUAUCGCAUGGAGGCCUGGGGCGGCCCAGAGGAGCUGGGCCUGGCGCCCGCGCCCAACCCCCGGCGGGUCAUGUCCCAGGAGCACCUGCUGGGCGAUGGUGGCCGUUCGCGCUACGAGUUCACGCUGCCGCGCGCGCGCCUGGUGUCGCAGGAGCACCUGCUGCUGUCCUCGCCCGAGGCCCUGCGCCAGAGUCGCGAGCACCUGCUGUCGCCCCCGCGCAGCCCCGCGCUGCCCCCCGACCCCACCGCCCGGGCCAGCCUGGCCGCCUCGCACUCCAACCUGCUGCUGGGGCCCGGGGGGCCCCCAACACCGCUGCGCGGGCUGCCGCCACCGUCCAGCCUGCACGCCCACCACCACCACGCCCUGCACGGCUCGCCGCAGCCGGCCUGGAUGUCCGACGCCGGCGGGGGCGGGGGCACACUGGCCCGCAGGCCGCCCUUCCAGCGCCAGGGCACGCUGGAGCAGCUGCAGUUCAUCCCGGGCCACCACCUGCCCCAGCACCUGCGCACGGCCAGCAAGAACGAGGUGACUGUCUGAGGCCAGGGCCGGGUCUGGGGGGCUGCGGCCUCCCGGGCCCCCCGUCCCAGCCUGGAUCCCCCGACACAGGCGCACACAUGCCAGGGGCCUGGGGCCCAGAUCGGCCCUUGGACAGGAGUGAAAGCCUCCUUCUGGGAUGUCCUGGCAGACAAGAUUCCUCCUCCUAUUACUUCACUGCUUGAGCCAAGGCCUCCUUCCCAUGAUGUCAUCCCAGAGGAAGAGGCCGGCUCAUGAGGUCAUCACUAGCAAAAAUGUCUGUGUUCUGUGAUGUCAUCACAGGGACAAAGCCUCGUUCCCAUGAGGUCAUCACAGAGGAAGAGGCCGGCCCGUGAGGUCAGCGCUGGAGGCCAUGUCCAUGUUCUAUGGUGUCCUCAGAGGCUUCCUUCUUGUGGUAUAAUAACAGAGACGACGCCUUGUUCCAUGACAUUCCUUCCUGUGGUGUCACUGCAGAGACAAUCUCACCUGGAUGAUGUCAUCUCUAACUCCAAGGCCUCUUUUGGCAUCAUCGCCAUGGGGAAGAUAUUUUCUCCCUGUGUCUUUGCAGCAGAGAAGAUGCCUCUGUCCUAUGAUGUCAUCAUUACAGACAAAGCCAUCUUCCUGGGACACGUCGCAGGGGAAAAUGCCUCACCGAUUGUGUCCUCACUAGACAUAAGGUCCCCUUUUCACAACAUCAUCACAGGGACCCUGCCUCCUUCCUGUGAUGCCAUCACCAGAGAAGGUGCCUUGCCCUAUGACGUCAUCAGAGGGACCGUGCCUCUUCCUGUGAUGUCAUCACCAGAGAUGACCACCCACUCUGGGACCUCUCCAGGAGGAGGUCCCUUCUGUGAUGUCGCCCAGAUGCUAUGUGCUCUGAGAUGGCACAAAGAGAUGCCUCCACUGCUGCCACCAUGUUGUAGAAGGCAGGGCAGGCCCAGAGUCCAGGACCACCCCAGGGAAGAUGCCAGAGAGCAGAGAGGGGCCCUGUCCUGAGAUGUUGUCUGAAGGAAGCAUCGCUGGGGAGCCGCCCAUGUGGAGGGCCUCCUCCAGAGAUGAUGGUCUGUGUAGGCUGUUGGCAGUGACACCCCUACCCCCAAUGCUGUGAUGGCAUCACCAGAGCUUCCUCCUCAGAGGCACUGCCCACUCUGGAAGGCCAUCGGUAUUGGUGGUGUCACCAGAGUUACUGCCUUGUCCCACCAUGACUUAGCUUGGUUGCUCCCUCCCCAGACUCCAGGGACAUGUCCAGCAGGAUCUCUGCCAGACCCUCUGAGGGGAAAUGGGGCCUUGGAUCCCACAUCUGUGCCAUGACUCCUGGGAGACAGGACCUCCAGAUGGCCUUCUGCUCCCAGGAGGCCACUCUGGAUCACCAGGAUCCUGGAGUUCUGGCACUCAUAGGUGUCCCAUAGCCUGGCCUCACUUUUCUUUCUGCCAUAUCUAGAGACAAUCACCUCUGUCAACAAAGUCCUAGCCUUCUACUGGGGGGAGGUGCUUGGGGUACACCUACUCUUGCCCUCACUGACACUGUCAGCAUCACACAACACCCGCCACUCAUGAUGGCACCACACCCGGGGUCAAGUGUUACCCAUGUCUGAGGAUGGAAUCCUUCCCCAGGAUUACCUAUGACCCACAACUAUGGUAUCAUCUUCUUCCAGGAUUUACCAUGACUAAUGGUGUCACCAUCUGCCAAGACUCCCCAUAGCCAAUGGUGUCACCAUCCUCCAUGAUUCCUCACAACCAUGGUGUCAUCAUCUUUCAGGAGCCACCACAGCUGACGGUGUCAUCAUCUCCUAGAUUCCACCAUGACCAGUGAUGACAUUACCUUCCAGAAUCCACUACACCUGACAGAGACAUCCUCUACUGAAAUCCACUAGGACUGAUGAUUCCACCAUUUCCCAUAAUCCCUCAUGAUUUUGGUGUCAUCACCUCCCAAGACCCAUGAUGCCCAAUAGUGUCAUCAUCAUUUGCAGGGAUGCAUGGUGUCAUCAUCUCCAGGGAUCCACUUCAACCAUGUGCCACCACCUCCCAGGAUUUCAUUCAAACAUGUGCCACUACCUCCCAGUAUCCACUUCAACUAUGGUGUUAUCACCUGCCAGGAUCCACGAGAGCCAAUGCUGUCACCAUCCACUAGGAUCCACCAUAACCCUGGUGUCAUCAUCUCCUGUGAUCCAUGAGGUCCAGUGCUGUCACCAUCCACUAGGAUCCACCAUGACCCUGGUGUCAUCAUCUCCUGUGAUCCAUGAGGUCCAGUGCUGUCACCAUCCACUAGGAUCCACCAUAACCCUGGUGUCAUCAUCUCCCAGGAUCCAUGAGGUCCAGUGCUGUCUGUCACCAUCCACUAGUAUCCACCAUAACCCUGGUGUCAUCUUCUCCCAGGAUCCAUGAGGUCCAGUGCUGUCACCAUCCACUAGGAUCCGCCAUAACCCUGGUGUCAUCAUCCGUGAUCCAUGAGGUCCAGUGCUGUCACCAUCCACUAGGAUCCACCAUAACCCUGGUGUCAUCAUCUCCCAGGAUCCAUGAGGUCCAGUGUUGUCACCAUCUACUAGGAUCCACCAUGACCCUGGUGUUAUCAUCUCCCAGGAUCCAUGAGGUCCAGUGUUGUCACCAUCUAUUAGGAUCCACCAUGACCCUGGUGUUAUCAUCUCCCAGGAUCCAUGAGGUCCAGUGCUGUCACCACCCACUAGGAUCCACCAUAACCCUGGUGUCAUCCCAGAGUCCACUGCAACCAUGUGCCAUCAUCCCCCAAGAGCCAUCAUCUUAGGAGCCAAGUACCGUGACGGGCUGUAUUUCAGUUGUCCUCUGGGGCCGCAUGGUACUUACAGUUGUUCACUUAAGGGGAACCAGCACAACAGGCCAUAUUCCCGUUUCCACUAAAAGGACAGGGGUGGGGCCAGCUGUCCCCCUCUGAAGACUUCACCCCUACUCUGGCCCUCCUUAUGUCACUGCCUCACUCCUGACCGAGGAUGAUGCCUGCAUCAAUCCCACCACAGAUGUGGCCUCAGCCAACCUCACCUUACCCCCCGGUGAGGCACCCAGGCCCCUCCUGACAGCAGCGCUGUCCCUCACCCAGCCAUCUGAUUGGUGACAGGGUCAACCCAGCAACCUCUCAUUAUCACCAGAGAGGAAGCAUUUCAACCCUCAGGUGACGCCACUGCCCCCUGCCCAAUCCCUGUCACUUGGGCCCCUACCAGGAUCAGCACUCCACUGGCCCCGGCCAAAUUCUCCUCAGAGAUCCCUGACCCCCGCGGGAUAGGUCAAAGCUGGUGACCGACUGGGGCCUUCAGUGCUGUCUUCUGCUGGCCUCAUCCUGCAGCAGGGACACUGGAGAGCAAUGGUCCCUGCCAGCACAUCUGCGGGACCAGGGGUGCUCCUUCACCUCCCUCCCUAACACCUUAACACCCGGGGAGCCUCCGGGGGUGGCAGGAAGUCCCCAGCACCCAAUGCACAAUCUUCCCUCAAUUCUCUUUGUACAUAGCCAUGUUGCGGGGGCGGCCAUUCCCCCACUCUUAAAGGGCUACACGCCCCUCCCCCAGCCCCUAGGGCGAGGUGGGGGGGGCCUCUUCUUCCUCCCCUGGGCCGUCCCCCUCCCUCUUAUGUCUCCCCGCAAACACUGGCACCUCACACUCCUUCUUGUCAGGAGCUUGGGGCAGACAACUGGCCCUUGGUUCCCACCACACUGAGGAAAUGGGGGUUACCCAAAUCCACCUGGGCCCUGGUGCCAGUUUUUCAACCCCACGGCUUCUAGCUGCUCUGAGGGGCUCCUCCCAUCCCUUCCAGGGCCUCCCCAGCCCCGCACUGCUCAGGCCAACUGUGACUUCCCCAGAAAGGAGCCAGCUUGAGCACCCACCCCCUCCCAGCCCCCUCCCCUCUGCUCAACACCUCCGCGGAACACUCAGCUUUCUCCAGCUGCCGGGAUUUGGGGGUCUGGGCCUUUCAGCUUUUUUAUCCCCCCUCCACUAGCUCUAGCCCAGCCUGGAUUCCAGGGAUCCCACCCCUAGCCCUGUCCCUAUUCAGUUGGCACAGGCUGCCUGACCCUGGGGCCUUGAUUUGAUCUCAAAUAAGCCAUAGAGGAGAGAGGUCUUGAGGGGUGGGAGCAGGUGUGUACUGACAAUUCCCCUCCACAUGUCUUGAGCUGGGACCUCGUCAUCUGAGACUUCCCCAUGCCCCAACAAAUGCAAAUGCACACAAACCCAUGCAUACACAAGCACACACACACAGGCAUCUCCCCGUCUGGUUGGGGGAGCAUGGGAGGGGGCACUUCACAGGGAGAAGAUAAAUAGUUCCACACCUGAAGACCCUCCAACAGCUUCUGCCUCCCUCCUCAUCACUUCCUCUCUCCACCCCCUCUCCAACACUGGCCCCUUCCCCUAAUUAAUUCCCUGGUGAGGACAGCCAGAGGAGCUGCGACUUGGUAUUUUUUGGAAUAAAUAGACAUUUUCCUGA